ACUCAGUGGUUUCUUGGUGACACUGGAUAGAACAGCUCAAGCCUUGCCACUUCGGGCUUCUCACUGCAGCUGGGCUUGGACUUCGGAGUUUUGCCAUUGCCAGUGGGACGUCUGAGACUUUCUCCUUCAAGUACUUGGCAGAUCACUCUCUUAGCAGGGUCUGCGCUUCGCAGCCGGGAUGAAGCUGGUUUCCGUCGCCCUGAUGUACCUGGGUUCGCUCGCCUUCCUAGGCGCUGACACCGCUCGGUUGGAUGUCGCGUCGGAGUUUCGAAAGAAGUGGAAUAAGUGGGCUCUGAGUCGUGGGAAGAGGGAACUGCGGAUGUCCAGCAGCUACCCCACCGGGCUCGCUGACGUGAAGGCCGGGCCUGCCCAGACCCUUAUUCGGCCCCAGGACAUGAAGGGUGCCUCUCGAAGCCCCGAAGACAGCAGUCCGGAUGCCGCCCGCAUCCGAGUCAAGCGCUACCGCCAGAGCAUGAACAACUUCCAGGGCCUCCGGAGCUUUGGCUGCCGCUUCGGGACGUGCACGGUGCAGAAGCUGGCACACCAGAUCUACCAGUUCACAGAUAAGGACAAGGACAACGUCGCCCCCAGGAGCAAGAUCAGCCCCCAGGGCUACGGCCGCCGGCGCCGGCGCUCCCUGCCCGAGGCCGGCCCGGGUCGGACUCUGGUGUCUUCUAAGCCACAAGCACACGGGGCUCCAGCCCCCCCGAGUGGAAGUGCUCCCCACUUUCUUUAGGAUUUAGGCGCCCAUGGUACAAGGAAUAGUCGCGCAAGCAUCCCGCUGGUGCCUCCCGGGACGAAGGACUUCCCGAGCGGUGUGGGGACCGGGCUCUGACAGCCCUGCGGAGACCCUGAGUCCGGGAGGCACCGUCCGGCGGCGAGCUCUGGCUUUGCAAGGGCCCCUCCUUCUGGGGGCUUCGCUUCCUUAGCCUUGCUCAGGUGCAAGUGCCCCAGGGGGCGGGGUGCAGAAGAAUCCGAGUGUUUGCCAGGCUUAAGGAGAGGAGAAACUGAGAAAUGAAUGCUGAGACCCCCGGAGCAGGGGUCUGAGCCACAGCCGUGCUCGCCCACAAACUGAUUUCUCACGGCGUGUCACCCCACCAGGGCGCAAGCCUCACUAUUACUUGAACUUUCCAAAACCUAAAGAGGAAAAGUGCAAUGCGUGUUGUACAUACAGAGGUAACUAUCAAUAUUUAAGUUUGUUGCUGUCAAGAUUUUUUUUGUAACUUCAAAUAUAGAGAUAUUUUUGUACGUUAUAUAUUGUAUUAAGGGCAUUUUAAAAGCAAUUAUAUUGUCCUCCCCUAUUUUAAGACGUGAAUGUCUCAGCGAGGUGUAAAGUUGUUCGCCGCGUGGAAUGUGAGUGUGUUUGUGUGCAUGAAAGAGAAAGACUGAUUACCUCCUGUGUGGAAGAAGGAAACACCGAGUCUCUGUAUAAUCUAUUUACAUAAAAUGGGUGAUAUGCGAACAGCAAACCAAUAAACUGUCUCAAUGCUGA